GCGCCUGGAGCCGGCUCCGCGGCGGAGGGGCGGCGCCCCGACCCAGGGCCAGCACCGUGGGCACCGCCAGGCCGGCGCGUAUGGAGGCGGUGGGACGCCUGCGGCGCGGGGCGCUGCGUGUUGUUCCUGCCUCCUAGAUUUGAGCCAGAGAGAACCCAGUUAACUGGACGCCUGGUGUGGCCCUGGUGGAGAAUGUUCUCCCCUCUCCCUGGCUUGUUUCCUCAUCUCGCAAACAGGGACAAGGAUGGACUCUCCCUUAAAGGGUCUUGAGAAAUAGCUGAGGGCUCUGGGCCUGCUGGCCCGAGGAGGCUGAGCCAGAUCUUGGGAAGGGUUCUGCAGGGCUUGGUAGCAGGAGGGAAGGAGGUAGCAGGAGGGAAAGAGGGGCCACGGCUGCCAGUGGGUCCCCGUGCUGUGGGCCGCGGGCCUGGUGGGGGUGGUAGCGACUCAGGACACAUGGAGGCAGGGGCAACCUGUCCCCAUUUCGCAGAUGGGAAGCCUGAGGCUUUGGCUUCAGGGAGUUCUCAGUGCCCAUCCCUGGGGAUCCUUAACCCUUGCUCUCAGGGCCCUACCUGGUGACCUCACUGGGGGCGUGUGGUUAUGGAGGGGUUUUCUCCCUUGGGGGACAGCCACCAGGCAGGGCAGAGCCACAUAGUGGUGCCAGGGCAUCAUUGCUUUGCUCUCACCUGGGGCAGGGGUAGGGGCCCUAGGCUGCAGAGACAAGUGGGAUGUGUGGCAAGACCCUGGUCCAGCCUCUCCCUGGACCCCUAACCCCAUUCUAGCCUGGGCUGUGACCCCUGAGCGUAGCCCAGGCUAACCCCCUGAUUCCGGCAGAUGUGUGGCAUCCUUAGGCCUUCAGUGGGGGGUAGUGUGGGGUGGUUCGGAGCCUCCUCCCUCCCAGUAGCCUGCAGCCCUGAGGACCUGUGCAGGGCCACUAGGCAGCAGGUCCAGGCCACGUGCUGGUGCCUGUGGGGUCUUCCUGGGUCCCUGGCAGCUGUAGGUGUGAGGGGUUGGUCAGCCCCUCAGGGAGAGGCCCAAUACUGUGGUUUCUCUGGUGCUUUUCUUCCUUUCUUUCUGUAAACAUGAGCUCGGCUCCCGUGUGCACACACACAGGGACAUCCUGCUGCCCCAAGAGGGACCCAGGUGUUUGUGUGCUGUUAGCACGUGGUGGCUUCCCUCACCCACACUCAGAGCCUGUGCUCCCUCCAGUCGGGCAAGGUGGGGACUGGCGGGACCAGGGACAGUAUCCUUGUCUCCACCUUUACCUCCUUCUGGGGGUCCCACCCCACCACCGGUUUUUUUUUUUUUUUUUGAGACGGAGUUUUGCUCUUGUUGCCCAGGCUAGAGGGCAAUGGAGCGAUCUCGGCUCACUGCAACCUCUGCCUCCAGGGUUCAAGCGAUUCUCCUGCCUCAGCCUCCCGAGUAGCUGGGAUUACAGGCAUGCACUUCCAUGCCUGGCUCAUUUUUUAUUUUUUUAUUUUUAGUAGAGAUGGGGUUUCUCCAUGUUGGUCAGGCUGGUCUUGAACUCCUGACCUCAGGUGAUCCGCCCGCCUUGGCCUCCCAAAAUGCUGGGAUUACAGGAGUGAGCCACUGCGCCUGACACCCACCGCCCAUUUUAACCUUCCCAGAACCAUGCAGUGGACAGAGCCUGAGGUGUGGCGGCUGCUCUGAGCCCAUGAGCACUGGCUGCCACCCAGGGUGUGGAGGGCAGGCAGGGAGGAGCCCACUGUCCCAGGUAGCCACCCUCUGAGUCCAGGGGCCCAGGCCUCAAGCCCUACCUGCACCUGGGCUGAAGCUCCAAGGGCCCAGCCUGCCUGGUGGGCAGCUGGGAAGGGGGUGCUGGGGCUGGGGCAGGGGCACAGGUGAGAGGGGGUGGGUUGGGGAAUGGAGGGCUCUGCUGGGCGAGGGGCCCUGAAGUGCCUUUCCUUGGGUAGCAGGCAGUAGUGACAGGGCCGGGCUUGGGUUGAGUCUAGGGGGCUGGAGAGUCUGCUAACAGCUGGGUCACAGCCAGGGCCAGCAGUGCGGGGACCCCUCAGCAGCAGUGCCCAAAUACAGCUUGGGUCACUUGUGUCACCCCUCAUCGUGCUCAUGGGGUAACAAAGAGGCCGGCACCUUGCUCAAGGCCUCCCAGCCCUUCCGUAGAGAGGGAAGGGGGCUGCGUGCUCCUGGAACCCCUUUGCCUGGGAGCUUUGGGGUCAUGAGACCCAGAAAGGGAGAGAGGCAGGCGUGGAGGUGCCUUGGGUUGCUGUGGCCCCCCCUGCCGCCUCCCCUCUUCAGGGCCCUGUCAUGGUGUGAACCCACUCCUGGCCACCUGUGCUGUCACCACCUUGGCAUGUGUGCCUGAUGGCUGGCCCAUUGGCGUGUUCUGUCCCCGCCUCCCUGAGCUCCUGGAGGGGCAGAGCUGGCCUGUUUAUCCCCGAGCCUGGCUGAGACCUGUGUGAGCAGUGGAGACACAGUGGCGGGGGGACACUGGUGGACAGGGGGCUGCUGACAGGCAGGAGACUUUCUGCAGAAAGCAAGAGGCGAUUAGGGUGGCCCACGGCCGCGUGUGGGGCCAGGCCCCUCACCUCCCUGUGCUGGCAGCACUGACCGAGUGCCUGGGCCCCAUUCCCUGAGGAUGGGCCACCCAGAGACACCUGGGCUCAGAUGUUCACAGUGGCUGAGAAUCGGAAGAGGAGAGGGCAGCUGUCCUGGGGUGGAGUUUCCGCAGAUCACAGCAGAUGCUGUGUGCUGUGGACCCACCUGGGGUUCAUGGAGUGGGCCACGGGGCCCAGCCCUAAGCACUGCUGCGCCCAGGGUCGCCGCGCCUCCUGCUGAGGGGUCCCCGUGCCACUGGCUCUCACCAUUGCCCUCGCCUGCCGAUGGCCUCUGCUGCCCAGCCUGGGGCCAGCUCUACCGCCUGAGCCCCCUGCCCCACUCCAGGACUCACCGUACCCCGAUGGGGUAACGUGACACAGGCCCCACACGUCAGAGGCCGCUGUCCCCACGGCCACUGCCCGUGACCCCUGGCCCAAGGCAGCUGGAGUUGGUUCAGUUCAAGUUCAUUCUUCCUCUGGCCCUUGGGGGCUUGGGGCCCACCUCUGAGUGAAGGGGGCUGUCUGCCCAUCCACCAAUGUGGAGAGGGCGCCCCCGGUGUGGGGUCCAGCUCUGGACACUGCUUGGCGGCCGGGUUCACUUUGAGUUUUUAAGUUUUCUUUGCUGAGCUUUUUUGGUUGUUCUUUUUAUUUUUUGCCUCUUUAUGACUAUCCAGCUCUGAGAGACGGGAGUUUGGAGUUGCCCGCUUUACUUUGGUUGGGUUGGGGGGGGCGGCGGGCUGUUUUGUUCCUUUUCUUUUUUAAGAGUUGGGUUUUCUUUUUUAAUUAUCCAAACAGUGGGCAGCUUCCUCCCCCACACCCAAGUAUUUGCACAAUAUUUGUGCGGGGUAUGGGGGUGGGUUUUUAAAUCUCGUUUCUCUUGGACAAGCACAGGGAUCUCGUUCUCCUCAUUUUUUGGGGGUGUGUGGGGACUUCUCAGGUCGUGUCCCCAGCCUUCUCUGCAGUCCCUUCUGCCCUGCCGGGCCCGUCGGGAGGCGCCAUGGCUCGGAUGAACCGCCCGGCCCCGGUGGAGGUGAGCUACAAACACAUGCGCUUCCUCAUCACCCACAACCCCACCAACGCCACGCUCAGCACCUUCAUUGAGGACCUGAAGAAGUACGGGGCUACCACUGUGGUGCGUGUGUGUGAAGUGACCUAUGACAAAACGCCGCUGGAGAAGGAUGGCAUCACCGUUGUGGACUGGCCGUUUGACGAUGGGGCGCCCCCGCCCGGCAAGGUAGUGGAAGACUGGCUGAGCCUGGUGAAGGCCAAGUUCUGUGAGGCCCCCGGCAGCUGCGUGGCUGUGCACUGCGUGGCGGGCCUGGGCCGGGCUCCAGUCCUUGUGGCGCUGGCCCUUAUUGAGAGCGGGAUGAAGUACGAGGACGCCAUCCAGUUCAUCCGCCAGAAGCGCCGCGGAGCCAUCAACAGCAAGCAGCUCACCUACCUGGAGAAAUACCGGCCCAAACAGAGGCUGCGGUUCAAAGACCCACACACGCACAAGACCCGGUGCUGCGUUAUGUAGCUCAGGACCUUGGCUGGGCCUGGUCGUCAUGUAGGUCAGGACCUUGGCUGGACCUGGAGGCCCUGCCCAGCCCUGCUCUGCCCAGCCCAGCAGGGGCUCCAGGCCUUGGCUGGCCCCACAUCGCCUUUUCCUCCCCGACACCUCCGUGCACUUGUGUCCGAGGAGCGAGGAGCCCCUCGGGCCCUGGGUGGCCUCUGGGCCCUUUCUCCUGUCUCCGCCACUCCCUCUGGCGGCGCUGGCCGUGGCUCUGUCUCUCUGAGGUGGGUCGGGCGCCCUCUGCCCGCCCCCUCCCACACCAGCCAGGCUGGUCUCCUCUAGCCUGUUUGUUGUGGGGUGGGGGUAUAUUUUGUAACCACUGGGCCCCCAGCCCCUCUUUUGCGACCCCUUGUCCUGACCUGUUCUCGGCACCUUAAAUUAUUAGACCCCGGGGCAGUCAGGUGCUCCGGACACCCGAAGGCAAUAAAACAGGAGCCGUGGCCGUGUGUGUGGAGUGGGCUACAGCGUCAGGCGGGGCGGGCUGGUGGCCUGGGGGCCCCAGAGGCUGCUGUCUGGAUCCUGGGCUGGUGCCCAGGAUGGGGCUCCCGCGUGCUCUUGCGCUGCCCUCUGGUGGCCGCUCUGGGUCCUUGCACCCCGACCCAGGGGCCAGCCUGCCCUGUCCUGUCCUGAUACCGAGGUGGGAGCCCUGCCUUGGCCAGGGUGGCCGUGUUGACGGUUCUUGGGACUGUGACAUUGGAAGGCGAGGCAGGUCACCAGCACUGUCCUCUGCAGGAUGGGCUGGGAUUCAUUUGGCAGCUUCUCAGGGCCUGUGUCCGGCUGGUUGGUCCCUGUGCUGCCCAAACCAGGUGUCCACAUUUCCGGCUCCGAGGCGCAGAGAAGGGGGCAGGUGGUGGCUUGGGUGGAGGAAGUCACCAUCCAUCAGCCCAGGGAGGGAGGGUGCCACCUGGGCACCUGGGGCUGGAUGUGAGAGGCCUGGACCAGGGCCCGCCGGAGGGCGUGGACCAGAUGCUCAUGUGUUCCUGGGUGCAGUGUCUGUGUUGGGGGCUGGCCCCACCCUGGGCCGGGGUGCAUGGAGGGCAUGGCCCCAGCGGGGAGGAAGGUGGGCCUAGGGCUGGCUCCAGGGUGUGGAGAGCCUGGGAGUGGUCUCCGUCCUGGGGCCCCAGGAGGUUCCCGCAAGGAGCGACUGGGGCAGGUGCUGGAGGAGGUCAGUGGACAAGAUGGGGAGAUGUGGAAACCCCAAAAGCCCCUUCUCAGGCAGCCCUGCCCCCAAGACCGACAGAUGGCUAAGGGGGCCGCAGACCUGGCUCCCCCAGCUCCUGUGUGGAGAAAGGGCAACAGCUGUCCCGGAUGGUUAUUCUCUCCUUUCCUCAAACACAUUUGGAACUCAAGUAAAUCCAAUGCAUGUUGGGUGAA